UCAUACUGGAGAGAAACCCUACACAUGUGAAGAAUGUGGCAAAGCCUUUAACCAGUUCUCAAACCUUACUACACAUAAGAGAAUCCAUACUGCAGAGAAAUUCUAUAAAUGUACAGAAUGUGGUGAAGCUUUUAGCCGGUCCUCAAACCUUACUAAACAUAAGAAAAUUCAUACUGAAAAGAAACCCUACAAAUGUGAAGAAUGUGGCAAAGCUUUUAAGUGGUCCUCAAAGCUUACUGAACAUAAGUUAACUCAUACUGGAGAGAAACCCUACAAAUGUGAAGAAUGUGGCAAAGCCUUUAACUGGCCCUCAACCCUUACUAAACAUAACAGAAUUCAUACUGGAGAGAAACCCUACAAAUGUGAAGUAUGUGGCAAAGCCUUUAACCAGUUCUCAAACCUUACUACACAUAAGAGAAUUCAUACUGCAGAAAAACCGUACAAAUGUGAAGAAUGUGGCAAAGCUUUUAGCCGGUCCUCAAACCUUACUAAACAUAAGAAAAUUCACAUUGAAAAGAAACCCUACAAAUGUGAAGAAUGUGGCAAAGCUUUUAAGUGGUCCUCAAAGCUUACUGAACAUAAGAUAACUCAUACUGGAGAGAAACCCUACAAAUGUGAAGAAUGUGGCAAAGCUUUUAACCAUUUCUCAAUCCUUACCAAACAUAAGAGGAUUCAUACUGGAGAGAAACCCUACAAGUGUGAAGAAUGUGGCAAAGCUUUUACCCAAUCCUCAAACCUUACUACACAUAAGAAAAUUCAUACUGGAGAGAAAUUCUACAAAUGUGAAGAAUGUGGCAAAGCUUUUACCCAAUCUUCAAACCUUACUACACAUAAAAAAAUUCAUACUGGAGGAAAACCCUACAAAUGUGAAGAAUGUGGCAAAGCUUUUAACCAGUUCUCAACUCUUACUAAACAUAAGAUAAUUCACACUGAGGAGAAACCCUACAAAUGUGAAGAAUGUGGCAAAGCCUUUAAGUGGUCCUCAACCCUUACUAAACAUAAGAUAAUUCAUACUGGAGAGAAACCCUACAAAUGUGAAGAAUGUGGCAAAGCUUUUAAACUGUCCUCAACCCUUUCUACACAUAAGAUUAUUCAUACUGGAGAGAAACCCUACAAAUGUGAAAAAUGUGGCAAAGCUUUUAACCGAUCCUCAAACCUUAUUGAACAUAAGAAAAUUCAUACUGGAGAGCAACCCUACAAAUGUGAAGAAUGUGGCAAAGCAUUUAACUAUUCCUCACACCUUAAUACACAUAAGAGAAUUCAUACUAAAGAGCAACCCUACAAAUGUAAAGAAUGUGGCAAAGCUUUCAACCAAUAUUCAAACCUUACUACACAUAACAAAAUUCAUACUGGAGAGAAACUCUACAAACCUGAAGAUGUGACAGUGAUUUUGACAACACCUCAAACUUUUUCAAACAUAAAAUAAAUUAUACUGGUGAGAAAUUCUAGAAAUGUAAAGAAUGUGAUAAAGGCUUUACAUGGUUGUCACACUUGAUUGUAGGUAAGAUAAUUUACAUUGGAGUAAACUUCUACAAGUGUGAAGAAUGUGGCAAAACUUUUAAUUAAUGCUCGUACCUUAUUGCACAGGAAAGAAUUUUUACUUGGAAAAAGGUAUAUACACAAAGAAUGUGGAAAAGCCAUUAAUAUGUGCUCAUAUCUUACUCAACAUCAGAGAGUCUGUACUUAAUAAAACCAUUAUAGAUGCAACUAGUGUCAAAAGAUCUUUCAGAAAAUAAAAGCCUUUAAAGUGAAGAAGAUAAUUCAUUCUGAAGACAAACAUUACAAAUAUUAAGAGGGUUGUAGUACCAUUACUUGCAUCACAGAUCUUAUUGUACACAUUUUGUACUAAAGAAAACCCUGAAGCAGUUGCUCAAAUACUGUUCAACAUCAGAAAAUUUAUAUUGGAAAAAACCCCUGGAAAAUGUAAUAAAUUUGUAAAAACAGUUUUGAAAAACUACAGCUUAUAAAACAUGAGGGUCUAUAAUGCUUGGUUGAUAGUACAAAGUUUAUUCAACAUCAGGGAAUUUAUAUUGGAGAAAAACCCUACAAAUGUAAUCAGUUUGGAAAAACAUUUUUAAAAAAACCACAGCAUAGAAAACACCACAGGGUUCAUACUAAAAUAUGUUUUUGCAGAUGCAGUAAAAAUGAAAAAAAUUUAAUCCGAAAUUAAGUUUAUGUAAAUAUCUGAGAAUUCACAGUAGAAAUAUCUAAGGCGCGGACACUUCAGACAUUACACUAAAUCAGUGCUAAGUACAGAAAACAACACAAAAUAAAACUUGGUGGAUAAAUUAUUUGUAUAUAACAUUAAAAGAAGUAGAAGAUUUUCAGUUAUAAUUACAAUUAAAGUAUACUUUUAUCUUGAAAAAAUUACUGAUUUUUAAAUUAGUGAAUAAUGAUGUAAUUAAACUCUCAAAUAACUUUAUGCUCUUUUUUCAUUCCUGCUAUAUUCACAUGUGAAAGCAUGUGACCAAUUGUUGCUGCACCAAAGAUAUGAGAGAUUCUUUUAUUAGGUGGGCAUUAUUUAAAACAUUUUUUAUGGAACAGUAAGGAUAUUAAAGUGUAAGAUGCAGCCAGGCAUGGUGGCUCAUGCCUAUAAUCCCAGCACUUUGGGAGGCUGAGGCCGGUGGAUCACCUGAGGUCAGGAGUUUGAGACCAGCCUGACCAACAUGGUGAAACCCUGUCUUUACUAAAAAUACAAAAAUUUACCAGGCACCUAUAAUCCCAGCUACUUCAAAGGCUGAAGCAGGAGAAUCACUUGAACCUGGAAAGUGGAGGUCUCAGUGAGCCGAAAUCAUACCAUUGCACUCCAACCUGGGCAACAAAAGUCAAACUCCAUCUCAAAAAGAAAAAAAAAAAAAAAAAAGAUGCGUGAUGAAAAUGUAACUGGAGAGGCUCUUUGUGGUUAACUUAUAAAGGAGUGAUGCAGGAGAUAGGUUUUCAGAGUAAUAUUCUUCUGCAUUAUAGUGACAAAAGUUUUUUAUUUUAGUUAAAAUUGGUUAAAUUAGUAAGUCAUUUUACUUAUUGUAAUUUUAUGUAAUUAAAUGUACAUUUUUAAAUUUUUAGAUUACAUGUAAAUAUAACUUUUAAAAAAAUGUGUUAAGACCAUUGUACAUUCAAUGAAGCAUUAUUAUGCUUCUAACUUUAACCUAUUUCACCUUACUCAAGAGUGUAUGUAAAAGAUGGUAACAAUAUACUAUUUGGUAACAUAAUGGACUAACAUUUCUAUUAAUCUAUUUCACCAGUGGCUUUCAACUGCAAAUAAGUUAAAGAAUAUUUUUCUAUAGGUUAAAUAUUCUUUUUUGUCUUAUUUAAACUUACUGUUCUUAAUUUCUGUGGGUACAUAGUAUGAUUUUAAUUACCUUAUUUUAUUCUUUGUGCUAUUCAUAAUUUUUUUUGUUUGUUUGGUUUUUUUUUUUGAGACAGAGUCUUGCUCUCGCCCAGGCUGGAGUGCAGUGGCGCGAUCUUGGCUCACUGCAAGCUCCGCCUCCCAGGUUCACUCCAUUCUCCUGCCUCAGCCUCCCAAGUAGCUGGGACCACAGGCGCCCACUACUUGUUUGGGUUUUUUUUUGGAGAUGGAGUCUCGCUCUGUCACCCAGGCUGGAGUACAGUGGCAUGAUCUUGGCUCACUGCAACCCCCACCUCCCCGGUUCAAGUGAUUCUCCUGCCUCAGCCUCCCGAAUAGCUGGGAUUACAGGCGUCCACCAUCACACCAGGCUAAUUUUUGUAUUUUUAGUAGAGAUGGAGUUUCACCAUGUUGGCCAGGAUGGUCUCGAUCUUCUGACCUCAUGAUCUGCCUGCCUCGGCCUCCCAGAGUUCUGGGACCACAGGCAUGAGCCACUGCACCUGGCCAAAUGUGUAUAUAUUUAUGCAAUAUAUAACAUGUUUUGAUACAGGCAUAUAAUAUGUAUUAGUCACAUCAGGAUAAAGUAUCUAUUACCUUCAGCAUUUAUCCUUUGUAUUACAAGCCAAUUCUACACUUCAUUAUUUUAAUGUACAAUUAAAUUGUUAUUGACUACAGGGUCAUUUUAAUUAUAAAAAUUAUAUAGAAGUAUAAAUAAAGUCCAUACAUUCCUGAGUCAUGAAUAAA